GGCUAACUACUAGAAUCCAGAUGUGAAUAAGACACACUCUUCGCCAUUCAGUAACUCACAGCCUAGUGGGGAAGCUGACCGAACAGUAAUCAAUGACAGCUUGAUAGGUUUGAUAAUUGAGGCAGAUUGUUUUGUUUUGUUUUGUUUUUUUUGAGAUGGAGUCUUGCUCUGUUGCUCAGGCUAGAGUGCAGUGGCACAAUCUCGGCUCACUGCAACCUCCGCCUCCUGGGUUCAAGUGAUUCUCCUGCCUCAGCCUCCCAUGUAGCUGGGACUGCAGGCGCCCGUCACCAUGCCCGGCUAAUUUUUGUAGAGACGGGGUUUUGCCAUGUUGGUCAGGCUGGUCUUAAACUCCUGACCUCAGUGCCCACCUUGGCCUCCCAAAGUGUUGAAAUUACAGGCAUGACCCACCGCGCCUGGCCACUGAGGCAGUUUUGAGGGGUUGUGAGUACCUCACGCGAGAUUAAUGAAACCGUGUCAAUCAUUCCAUUUCUCGGGCAUUCUAUGCAGCCGACUUCAUAGGCAUAGUUUGUGCUUUUUAGGAGCAUGCUUUUAGAGGAGGCGCUUCGGAAUCAUUUUAUGGGUCAUAGACAAAAAGACAGAGUGAAUAGGAAGCCACUAAAGUAUACUUUGCGGCCGAGCGCGGUGGCUCACUUCUGUAAUCCCAGCACUUAGGGAGGCUGAGGCGGGCAGAUCACAAGGUCAGGAAAUUGAGACCAUCUUGGCCAACACAGUGAAACCGCAUCUCUACUAAAAAUACAAAAAAUUAGCCGGGCAUGGUGGCACGCACCUGUAGUCCCAGCUCCUCCAGAGGCUGAGGCAGGAGAAUUGCUUGAACCCGGGAGGUGGAGGUUGCAGUGAGCCGAGAUCACGCCACUGCACUCCAGCCUGGGUGACAGAGUGAGACGCCACCUCAAAAAGAAAAAAAAAAAAGAAUUGCAGAAAAAGCUCUUCCUUCAAAAGUUCCUGCCUUUUCCGACAAGGACAGCCUGGGGGAUGAGAUGUUGGCGGCUGCGCUCCUAAAGGCCAAGUCCCAGCACGUGUUGUUUCAGGAGCUGGUAACCUUUGAGGAUGUAGCUGUGUACUUCAUCCGGAAGGAGUGGAAGCGUUUGGAACCUGCUCAGAGGGACCUCUAUAGAGAUGUGAUGCUGGAGAAUUACGGGAAUGUGUUCUCACUGGAUCGUGAGACCAGGACUGAAAAUGAUCAAGAAAUUUCUGAAGACACAAGAUCACAUGGGGUCCUACUGGGAAGAUUUCAAAAGGAUAUUUCUCAGGGUCUCAAGUUUAAAGAAGCCUAUGAACGAGAAGUCAGUCUGAAAAGGCCGCUGGGGAACUCCCCUGGAGAAAGACUGAACAGGAAAAUGCCAGAUUUUGGUCAAGUGACAGUUGAGGAGAAGCUAACCCCCAGGGGAGAGAGAAGCGAGAAAUAUAAUGAUUUUGGGAACAGCUUCACUGUGAAUUCCAACCUUAUCUCACAUCAGAGACUCCCCGUGGGAGACAGACCCCAUAAGUGUGAUGAAUGUAGCAAGAGCUUUAAUCGAACUUCAGACCUUAUUCAACAUCAGAGAAUCCACACUGGGGAAAAGCCCUAUGAAUGUAAUGAGUGUGGGAAGGCCUUCAGCCAGAGCUCACACCUUAUUCAGCAUCAGAGAAUCCACACUGGGGAAAAACCUUAUGAAUGUAGUGAUUGUGGGAAAACCUUCAGCUGUAGCUCUGCCCUCAUUCUGCAUCGGAGGAUCCACACGGGGGAGAAACCCUAUGAAUGUAAUGAGUGUGGGAAGACCUUCAGCUGGAGCUCCACCCUCACCCACCAUCAGAGAAUCCACACUGGUGAGAAACCCUACGCCUGCAAUGAAUGUGGGAAGGCCUUCAGCAGGAGCUCAACCCUUAUUCACCAUCAGAGAAUCCACACUGGAGAAAAACCCUAUGAAUGUAAUGAAUGUGGGAAAGCCUUCAGCCAGAGCUCACACCUCUAUCAGCACCAGAGAAUCCACACUGGAGAGAAGCCCUACGAAUGUAUGGAAUGUGGAGGAAAGUUUACCUACAGUUCAGGCCUUAUUCAGCAUCAAAGAAUCCACACCGGGGAGAACCCCUAUGAAUGUAGUGAGUGUGGGAAAGCCUUCAGGUACAGCUCGGCUCUUGUUCGCCAUCAGAGAAUUCACACUGGAGAGAAGCCUUUGAAUGGGAUCGGCAUGAGCAAAAGCUCCCUCAGAGUUACGACCGAGUUAAAUAUCAGAGAGUCCACGUGAAAGAGCCACACACCCAUUUUCCUCACUUUCCCUGAGUCUCAAGAGCUCUUGCCUUACCCUAUAAAUCUCAACAGCUUAGGAUGUGUCCCUUUCAACUCAGACUUUUCAUUUUAGAGAAUGGGGCAGAUGGGGCAAAUCGUUGAAUUUUCCCAGAAAUCACACCAGCCUUAGAAAGCGUCAAGGCAAGUGGAUGGCGUGCUGGGAAUAGAAAGCAGCUCUGGGACCAGUUACCCCAUUUAGGAAAGGAGUUUGCACUAAACUGUUUUUCUCACAGCAGAGGAACCUUUCCAAGGUGGGGAUGGAAGCACAGUCGGGACAGAAUUCGAUGGAUUCCUUUAGUUGGAGUCCGCGUAGUCAGCACAGACAGCAGUGGAAAGGACGCUCUGGGUCCUGUUAUUUGCUAGGGAGGGUAAAGGGAGACUAUUUCAAAGCUACUGUUCCUAGUCCAGCUUUAAGUUUCGGUAAGAAACAUGCUGUUUUGUUUCAUGAUUUCGUUAAUUAUGGAAAUUUGGCAUUGAGGGAUUAUUUUAUUGAGGGUAGAAGAGAUUCCAGAAUCAUCAUCUGUGAUGAUGGUGUCCUUUAGGGCUCUUGGAGCAGCCAGACCAUGUUUCCAAGAGAAACCUGGUGAUAUUGCCAGCAGACCCCCUGCCAUCCCCCCCAGUUGUCCUGGGGCUGAAUGGGCAAAUCUGUCCAAACAGCUAGUAACCGGCUGUGAGGGAGAGGGUCAGAAGCACUUAGCGUUGGCCUCUGAUUGCUGUCCUCUCUUGUCCUCUUCCCACUCCAAUGAUGAAAAUGAUUUUCUCUAAAUGCCUGGGUAAGGAUGCUUUCAAGGAGCUCACUUGGCCUGCUUGCCCUGCCCUCUCACCUCUGACACCCAGCCCCAGGAGCCAGACCACUCCUGCCUCCACCUCUGACUCUUCAGCAGCUGAAGAUUAAUGCAGAGAAAGAGCAAAGCCCAAAAGGGAGAAAAAAAAAACAAAAAAACAAAAAAACGAAGCCCAGAGAAGGCAGGCUGUGCCUGAGCCUGGUAGCAGAGCUCGUUGCUGGGUGAGGAUGGCACUCCCCGAGUUUUCCCAACCGACGGGAUGACCUUCCAUUGUGUUUUCCCAACCCUGCUCAUCCUGUAGCAUAAAUGAAGUGCACUAUUAAACAGAAUAGUUUUUCAGAAGA